CCCCGCCUUUAUUCAGCUUCCGGUAGACGCUGGUAGGGUAAGGGAGCUAAGUAGAUCACUUCCGGGCGACUGUUGUUUUAUUUCCGGUUUAUGCGACCCGGCUGCGAUUUGCUGCUGAGGGCAGCAGCUACCGUCACUGCCGCCAUCAUGUCAGACUCGGACAGCGAGGAAGAUUCAUCUGGAGGUGGCCCAUUUACUUUAGCGGGUAUCCUUUUCGGCAACAUCAGUGGAGCGGGGCAGCUGGAGGGGGAAAGCGUCUUGGAUGAUGAGUGUAAGAAGCACUUGGCAGGCUUGGGGGCUUUGGGGCUGGGCAGCCUAAUCACUGAACUCACGGCAAAUGAAGAAUUGACUGGGACUGGCGGUGCCUUGGUAAAUGAUGAAGGGUGGAUUAGGAGUACAGAAGAUGCUGUAGACUAUUCAGACAUCAAUGAGGUGGCAGAAGAUGAAAGCCAAAGACACCAGCAGACGAUGGGGAGCUUGCAGCCCCUUUACCACUCGGAUUAUGAUGAAGAUGACUAUGAUGCUGAUUGUGAAGACAUUGAUUGCAAGUUGAUGCCUCCUCCACCUCCACCCCCGGGACCAAUGAAGAAGGAUAAGGACCAAGAUGCUAUUACCUGUGUGUCUGAAAGUGGAGAAGACAUCAUCUUGCCCUCCAUCAUUGCCCCUUCCUUUUUGGCCUCAGAGAAAGUGGAUUUCAGUAGUUACUCUGAUUCAGAAUCUGAGAUGGGACCUCAGGAAGCAACACAGGCAGAAUCUGAGGAUGGAAAGCUGACCCUUCCAUUGGCUGGGAUUAUGCAGCAUGAUGCCACCAAGCUGUUGCCAAGUGUCACCGAACUUUUUCCAGAAUUUCGACCUGGAAAAGUGUUACGCUUCCUACAUCUUUUUGGACCAGGGAAGAAUGUCCCAUCUGUUUGGCGGAGUGCUCGGAGAAAGAGGAAGAAGCAUCGUGAGCUGAUACAGGAAGAGCAGAUCCAGGAGGUGGAAUGCUCAGUAGAAUCAGAAGUCAGCCAGAAGUCUUUGUGGAACUAUGACUAUGCUCCACCACCACCCCCAGAGCAGUGUCUCGCUGAUGAUGAAAUCACGAUGAUGGUUCCUGUGGAGUCCAAAUUUUCCCAAUCAACUGGAGAUGUAGAUAAAGUGACAGAUACCAAACCAAGAGUGGCUGAGUGGCGUUAUGGGCCUGCCCGACUGUGGUAUGAUAUGCUGGGUGUCUCCGAAGAUGGCAGUGGGUUUGACUAUGGCUUCAAACUGAGAAAGACACAACAUGAACCUGUGAUAAAAUCUAGAAUGAUGGAGGAAUUUAGGAAACUUGAGGAAAGCAAUGGCACUGAUCUUCUGGCUGACGAAAACUUCCUGAUGGUGACACAGCUGCAUUGGGAGGAUUCUAUCAUCUGGGAUGGGGAGGAUAUCAAACACAAAGGGACAAAACCUCAGGGUGCAAGCCUGGCAGGCUGGCUUCCUUCUAUUAAGACUAGGAAUGUAAUGGCUUACAAUGUUCAGCAAGGUUUUGCACCCACUCUGGAUGAUGACAAACCUUGGUACUCCAUUUUUCCCAUUGACAAUGAGGAUCUGGUGUAUGGACGCUGGGAGGACAAUAUCAUUUGGGAUGCUCAGGCCAUGCCCCGGCUGUUGGAACCUCCUGUUUUGGCACUUGAUCCCAAUGAUGAGAACCUCAUUUUGGAAAUUCCUGAUGAGAAGGAAGAGGCCACCUCUAACUCCCCCUCCAAGGAGAGUAAGAAGGAAUCAUCUCUGAAGAAGAGUCGAAUUCUCUUGGGCAAAACAGGUGUCAUCAGGGAGGAACCACAGCAGAACAUGUCUCAGCCAGAAGUGAAAGAUCCAUGGAAUCUCUCCAAUGAUGAGUAUUAUUUCCCCAAGCAACAGGGUCUUCGGGGCACCUUUGGAGGGAAUAUUAUCCAGCAUUCAAUUCCUGCUAUGGAAUUAUGGCAGCCCUUCUUUCCCACCCACAUGGGGCCCAUCAAAAUCCGGCAGUUCCAUCGCCCACCUCUGAAAAAGUACUCAUUUGGUGCACUCUCUCAGCCAGGUCCCCAUUCAGUCCAACCUUUGCUAAAGCACAUCAAAAAAAAGGCCAAGAUGAGAGAACAAGAGAGGCAAGCCUCAGGUGGUGGAGAGUUGUUUUUUAUGCGCACACCUCAGGAUCUCACAGGCAAAGAUGGAGAUCUUAUUCUUGCAGAAUAUAGUGAGGAAAAUGGACCCUUAAUGAUGCAGGUUGGCAUGGCAACCAAGAUAAAGAACUAUUAUAAACGGAAACCUGGCAAAGAUCCUGGAGCACCAGAUUGUAAAUAUGGGGAAACUGUUUACUGCCAUACAUCUCCUUUCUUGGGCUCUCUCCAUCCUGGCCAAUUACUGCAGGCACUUGAGAACAACCUUUUUCGUGCUCCAGUGUAUCUUCAUAAGAUGCCAGAAACUGAUUUUCUGAUCAUUCGGACAAGACAGGGUUACUAUAUUCGGGAAUUAGUGGAUAUUUUUGUGGUUGGCCAGCAGUGUCCCUUGUUUGAAGUUCCUGGGCCUAACUCCAGAAGGGCCAAUAUGCAUAUUCGAGACUUUCUACAGGUUUUUAUUUACCGCCUUUUCUGGAAGAGUAAAGAUCGGCCACGGAGGAUACGAAUGGAAGAUAUAAAAAAAGCCUUUCCUUCCCAUUCAGAAAGCAGCAUCCGGAAGAGGCUAAAGCUCUGCGCUGACUUCAAACGCACAGGGAUGGAUUCAAACUGGUGGGUGCUUAAGUCUGAUUUUCGUUUACCAACGGAAGAAGAGAUCAGAGCUAAGGUGUCACCAGAGCAGUGCUGUGCUUAUUAUAGCAUGAUAGCUGCAAAGCAACGACUGAAGGAUGCUGGCUAUGGUGAGAAAUCCUUUUUUGCCCCAGAAGAAGAAAAUGAGGAAGAUUUCCAGAUGAAGAUUGAUGAUGAAGUUCACGCUGCUCCUUGGAACACCACAAGGGCCUUCAUUGCUGCCAUGAAGGGCAAGUGUCUCCUAGAGGUGACUGGGGUGGCAGAUCCCACAGGGUGUGGUGAAGGAUUCUCCUAUGUGAAGAUUCCAAAUAAACCAACACAGCAGAAGGAUGAUAAAGAGCCACAGGCAGUGAAGAAGACAGUGACAGGAACAGAUGCAGACCUUCGUCGCCUUUCCCUGAAAAAUGCCAAGCAACUUCUACGUAAAUUUGGUGUGCCUGAGGAAGAGAUUAAAAAGUUGUCCCGCUGGGAAGUGAUUGAUGUGGUGCGCACAAUGUCAACAGAACAGGCUCAUUCUGGAGAGGGGCCCAUGAGUAAAUUUGCCCGUGGAUCAAGGUUUUCUGUGGCUGAGCAUCAAGAGCGUUACAAAGAGGAAUGUCAGCGUAUCUUUGACCUACAGAACAAGGUUCUGUCAUCAACUGAGGUCUUAUCAACUGACACAGACAGCAUCUCAGCUGAAGAUAGUGACUUUGAAGAAAUGGGAAAGAACAUUGAGAACAUGUUGCAGAACAAGAAAACCAGCUCUCAGCUGUCACGUGAAUGGGAGGAGCAGGAGCGGAAGGAACUACGGCGAAUGCUACUGGUAGCAGGCUCAGCAGCAUCAGGAAACAAUCACAGAGAUGAUGUCACAGCUUCCAUGACUAGCCUUAAGUCUUCUGCCACUGGACACUGUCUCAAGAUUUAUCGCACAUUUCGAGAUGAAGAGGGGAAAGAGUAUGUUCGCUGUGAGACAGUCCGAAAACCAGCUGUCAUUGAUGCCUAUGUGCGCAUACGGACUACAAAAGAUGAGAAAUUCAUUCAAAAAUUUGCCCUUUUUGAUGAAAAACAUCGGGAAGAGAUGCGGAAAGAACGGCGGAGGAUUCAAGAGCAACUGAGGCGGCUUAAGCGGAACCAGGAAAAGGAGAAGCUUAAGGGUCCUCCUGAGAAGAAGCCCAAGAAAAUGAAAGAGCGUCCUGACCUAAAACUGAAAUGUGGGGCAUGUGGUGCCAUUGGACAUAUGAGGACUAACAAAUUCUGCCCCCUCUAUUAUCAAACAAAUGUGCCACCUUCGAAACCUGUUGCCAUGACAGAAGAGCAGGAGGAGGAGUUGGAAAAGACAGUCAUUCAUAAUGAUAAUGAAGAACUUAUCAAGGUUGAAGGGACCAAAAUUGUCUUCGGGAAACAGCUAAUUGAGAAUGUGCAUGAGGUUCGCAGAAAAUCUCUGGUUCUCAAGUUUCCUAAACAGCAGCUUCCUCCAAAGAAGAAACGGCGAGUUGGAACCACUGUUCAUUGUGACUAUUUGAAUAUACCUCAUAAGUCCAUCCACCGACGCCGCACAGACCCUAUGGUGACGCUGUCAUCCAUCCUGGAGUCUAUCAUCAAUGACAUGAGAGAUCUUCCAAAUACACACCCUUUCCACACUCCAGUCAAUGCAAAGGUUGUAAAGGACUACUACAAAAUCAUCACUCGGCCAAUGGACCUACAAACACUCCGUGAAAAUGUGCGUAAAUGCCUCUACCCAUCUCGGGAAGAGUUCAGAGAGCAUCUGGAGCUAAUUGUGAAAAACAGUGCGACCUACAAUGGGCCAAAACAUUCAUUGACUCAGAUCUCUCAAUCCAUGCUGGAUCUCUGUGAUGAAAAACUUAAAGAGAAAGAAGACAAAUUAGCUCGCUUAGAGAAAGCUAUCAACCCCUUGCUGGAUGAUGAUGACCAAGUGGCAUUUUCUUUCAUUCUGGACAACAUUGUCACCCAGAAAAUGAUGGCAGUUCCAGAUUCUUGGCCAUUUCAUCACCCAGUUAAUAAGAAGUUUGUUCCAGAUUAUUACAAAAUGAUUGUCAAUCCAGUGGAUUUAGAGACCAUACGUAAGAACAUCUCCAAGCACAAGUAUCAGAGUCGGGAGAGUUUUCUAGAUGAUGUAAACCUUAUUCUUGCCAACAGUGUUAAGUAUAAUGGACCUGAGAGUCAGUACACUAAGACUGCUCAGGAGAUUGUGAACAUCUGUUACCAGACAAUUACUGAGUAUGAUGAGCAUUUGACUCAACUUGAGAAGGAUAUUUGUACAGCUAAAGAAGCAGCUUUGGAGGAAGCAGAAUUAGAAAGCCUGGACCCAAUGACCCCAGGGCCCUACACAUCUCAGCCUCCUGAUAUGUAUGAUACCAACACAUCCCUCAGUACGUCUCGAGAUGCCUCUGUAUUUCAAGAUGAGAGCAAUUUGUCUGUCUUGGAUAUUUCCACUGCCACUCCAGAAAAACAGAUGUGCCAGGGCCAAGGUAGGCUGGGUGAGGAAGACUCUGAUGUGGAUGUUGAAGGGUAUGAUGAUGAGGAGGAGGAUGGGAAACCUAAGCCUCCAGCCCCAGAAGGGGGAGAUGGUGAUCUUGCAGAUGAAGAGGAAGGAACUGUACAACAACCUGAAGCCAGUGUCCUGUAUGAGGAUUUGCUUAUAUCUGAAGGAGAAGAUGAUGAGGAAGAUGCUGGGAGUGACGAAGAAGGAGACAAUCCUUUCUCUGCUAUCCAGCUGAGUGAAAGUGGAAGUGACUCUGAUGUGGGAUAUGGUGGAAUAAGACCCAAACAACCCUUCAUGCUUCAGCAUGCUUCAGGAGAACACAAGGAUGGGCACGGAAAAUGAAGAAAGCAUGAUGUCCCAUGAGGGAGACGGUGGGGAGGCUUCCCAUGAUUUGGAGGAUAGCAACAUCAGUUAUGGGAGCUGUGAGGAGCCUGAUCCCAAGUUGAACACCCAAGACACAAGCUUCAGCAGCAUCGGAAAUUUCCAGCUGGGCAUGGUGGCUCACACCUGUAAUCUCAGCACUCUGGGAGGCCGAGGCGGGUGGAUCACCUGAGGUCAGUUCGAGACCAGCUUGGCCAACAUGUCGAAACUUCAUCUCUACUAAAAAUACAAAAAUUAGCCAGGUGUGGUGGUGCACGCCUGUAAUCCCCAGAUACUCGGGAGGCUGAAGCAGGAGAAUUGCUUGAACCCGGGAGGCAGAGGUUGCAGUGAGUGGAGAUCACGCCACUGCGCUCCAGCCUGGGCGAAAGAGUGAGACUCCAUCUCAAAAAAAAAGAAAAUUUCCAAGCAUGGUAUCAUCUCACUUUUCUAAUUUACAGGCUGGAACAGAUGAGAGCCCUCCUGCUGGGACAGAGAAUUGGGUUCUAGUGGACUCUGCUACACUUAAACCUAUGUGACAAACCGCCCAUUAUUUUAUUGUUUAUUUAAUUAUACAAUGCCUCGUUCCUAUAUGGAUUUGAGGCAAAUUACCAUAAAUUUUGAAACAGC